AUGAACACAGGGAGCUCAGGCUCCCACGGCGUCCGCCGCUCAGCCCGCCGCCAGGAACCCUCGGCUGCUUCCAUUGUUGCACCUCCGCUGUUGCCAUGUUGGAGGGAGAGCCCCCUGACCUCGGCUGCCUCCACUCUGGGGGCACUUUACAGACGCUGGGGCCGAUGCAACCCGCAGGAUGCGUGUCCUACCUGCGCUAGCUGCUGGCUCUGCUGCAACAUCCGACGUGUCUUGUGCCUGGCGACGUGGGCUGCUCGCUCCGCGCCUCCCGGGCUCGCUCUGCGGCUCCAGGCGCCUCUUGCACCAGCGCGAGAGGAGCUGGCCGGCCGCACGCCGCCUGCUCCCGGGCCGCUCCCCUCUCCAGGCUCCGCACAGACCCUAGGCUCCAAGGGGCAGAGGGAGAGGCAGCAAAGGGCGCAAGGACCAGCUUGUGGGGGUGGGGAGGGGUGCUCUCCGCCGAGAGCGUGCGCGAGCUCGCAGAGUCAGGCCACCCCGGGUGAGACAAUAGCGGCAGCAGCGGGCGAGAGAGGGGAAGCCAUCUCCCGGACACCCGGCGCACUGCACGGCGACGCGACGCUCGGCCAGACCCUGCCUGGACAGGCAGGCACCCGGCCGCCGGCUCCAGCCGCAGCGCCGAAUCCGCCGCGAGCCGGAGGGCGGGGCGGCUGCUGGAACCCGGGCCGCCCUUCGCCUCUCCCCUCCCCUUCCCCCUCCUCUUCUCUUCUCCUCUCCUCCUCUCCCCUCCGACUCCCGCCCCACUUGCCAUUGCGUGGGGGAAGAGAAACGCGCUGGCGUCAAGUUGUGCUCUGCAACCCAAGAGCCAGGAUUUCCACUCCCCACUUGGGUGAGGGUUUUUGCGGAUGGUCGUUAGUUUCCCCUGCUGGAACCCCUUGGCUUUGGGUCAGAGGAAAGCUCAAUCAUUCUGCUAGAAAUGACGGUGCUGAGGUCCAGUUAUCCGUUUCAGGAAUUUCUACCAUAAUUACGGUAGCGAUGUUCGGGGGAUCCCCUACCUUGAGGGUUAGGUUGGGGUAGAGAGAGGCUGUCUCCGGGCUUUACACGCUCAGUGUCAUUCGUCUUUCUGUCUCCUUCCUUCCUCCCUUUCUGGAAGGGGAGUCUCGUUUGUUUUUGUAUUCGCCCAGGUGGAUCUUCCGAGCUGCGAUCCAGGAAACAGCAGUCAACCUAAGUAGGGAGGGGAGAUAGAGGAUCCUCCAACCCAACUAGGGUAGUGAGAAAAAAAAGUAAAAAAAAAAAACCUUUCAUACAAUAUGUUAUAUUUAAAUUUUCUACUCUAAAUACCUUUCUUCCAGCAGUGGUCUCUGGAAGAAUUUUCCUAAAGGCUCCACCCAAAAGAAACCAUGAGUUGGCCAGCUCCUCGUUUGCAUUUGGUUUGCAUAGUACCAACGAUCACUAAUCUCAAAGUAUAUUUUCCUAAAAACGUGAAUCGUGUUUUCCUCCACUGCCCUCAUUUCUUCUUUCUUUCUCGACAGACUAUGAAGAUUAACACCUGGUCCUCAGCCUCUCAAGUAAAACCAUGAUUAAAUAAAUUUGUUAUGCUUUUCUCUGGUUAA